CCGGAGGCCAGAGGGGUUGGGGGCGCUGCACCUCCCUGGCUGUGUGGCCUUGGGGACUGCACUUCCCCCAGCCUGUUUCCUUCUCUGGGGAAUGGGGAGGAGGAGCCAGGGUGGCAGUGCCUGUGGUCAGGGUGGUGGAAGCCGGGUCCUUAUGGAAAAGCUGCUGUCCGCAUGUGCUCGGGGCGUCAUGGGUGCGGUGGCGCUGCCGCUCCGGGGCCCCCUGUGCUGCACUCCCUUGGAACCCAAGGGUCCUACGCCCAUUUCAUGGACGCGGGGACAGGUCGCGAGCGGGACCCACGCUGGCGGGUCUGAGUGGACGCGGGGACAGGCCGCGAGCGGGACCCACGCUGGCGGGUCUGAGUGGACGCGGGGACAGGUCGCGAGCGGGACCCACGCUGGCGGGUCUGAGUGGACGCGGGGACAGGUCGCGAGCGGGACCCACGCUGGCGGGUCUGAGUGGACGCGGGGACAGGUCGCGAGCGGGACCCACGCUGGCGGGUCUGAGUGGACGCGGGGACAGGUCGCGAGCGGGACCCACGCUGGCGGGUCUGAGUGGACGCGGGGACAGGUCGCGAGCGGGACCCACGCUGGCUGGGCUGAGCAUCACCUUGUCUGACUGAGUCCAGCCAGGCCCUGACCUUCCAUGCCUGGGCCCGGCGCCUGCCUGUGCCUGGACCCUGAGCAGAUGACGUGGACGGGUAGAGGGGGGCGCUGCAUCAGUUUCCAAAGACCCCCUCACUGGGCGGCUUACACAGUAGAAAUCCACCCCCUCACAGCUCUGCAGGCCAGAAGUCUGACCUUGAGGCGGGGGAAGGGCCGCGUCCCCUUGCAGGGCACUAGGGGUGGACCUGUCCUUGUCUCUUCCAGCUCCCAGCGGCUCUGAGCGUUCUUGGCUUGUGGUCGCCUCCCUCCAGUCUCUGCCUCCGUUUCCAUGUGGCCUUCUCUCUGUCUGUCUUCUCCUCUUCUGUCUCUUCUAAGGACAUGGUUGUUGGACUAGGGUCCACCCUAACCCAGCGCCCUCCCCAGCCACUGCCGCUGUUCCCAGUUCUCAGCCCAAAACUGAAGCACCACAAGCAAGUCCCUUAGCCAAGCCGUUACAGUCCUCGUCUCCCCGGGUGCUUGGCCUCCCUUCGAGGAUGGAACCGCCAGCCCCGCUGAGCACGAGCAGUACCUCUCAGGCAUCCGCGUUGCCCCCGGCAGGCAGGAGGAACUUGGCGGAAUCCUCAGGGGUCGGCAGGGUGGGUGCUGGCUCCAGGCCGAAGCCAGAGGCCCCGAUGGCAAAGGGUAAAAGCACCACCUUAACGCAGGGUGAGUAAGGGGCUGGGAGGCAGGAGGCCCCGGGGGCCCGCAGCUCUGGGACUCUCCCCUGGCCGCACUCUGCAGUGUGUGCGGUUUCAUCAUCAGCCCCGCCCGCCUUCCUCUCCGUCUCAUCUCUGUCCUCCGUGACACCUGCUCGCAGCCUCCUGGGGUCCUGGUGCGCUCUCUGUGUGGUGGCUGCAAAUGUCCUCAGGGCUAUGCUGUUUGCCGGCACCCAGCCCACCCCAUCCGCACGUCCUGCAGGUGCCUGCAGCCCAGCCCUGCAGCGUCCCGCUCAGCUCGGUCUGGCAGUUACAUCCUGUGGCUAGCAGUGGCCUGGCUUGGCCGUGGUCUGUGGGGCCUCCUGUUCUCCCGUGGUGUUUUGCGCUUCCUGCCUGUCGCUUUGACAACGUCGCGCUGUUGCUGUGGCACCCUGUGUCACCACAUACCGGAGAUGGUGCCCUAUGCCCCGUCCCCCCUGUGGUGUCCCGGUGACGGUGCCCUAUGCCCCGUCCCCUCCGCUGGUGUCCCAGUAUGCCCUGUCCCCCUGGUGGUGUCCAGGUGAGAGCGCCCUGUGCUCCGUCCCCCCCGGUGGUGGUCUGGUGACGAUGCCCUAUGACCUGAGGGCUCUGGUGCCUCCUAGGCUGGGAGCUCUUCCUGGGGGCUCCCUGGACCACACAGUCCUGUUUUAUGGCCUCACGUGUUUUCGGGAACAGGGAGCGAGCUUUCUUCUAGGCAACUGGCUGUCACCCACCAGGGGUUAGCCCCCUGGGUGAUCAUGGCCAGGCUGGGCAGGACGUGGGCUUAGGGCUUGUGAGGCCAACCCUGUGCCAGCUGGGAGGCCCAGGGCACUGGGAUGGCCAGGCUACGCAGUGAGCUGUCAGCUGUGCCAGGACAGACCCCAGGCUCCUGGCGGCCCUGCUUUGAUGCACGGCUCUGUCUCCCAACCUGGGGGCAGCCGAGUCCCCCCGCCUCGCCCCACUGCAGGAAACUGGCUGUCCCUGCCACCUGGGUGUGUGUAGAAAAAAGCUAGAGGUUCCCAUGGCUUUAUCGAGCUGGGCUCAGGGAACAAGCUGGGCUGCAAAGGGUUUUUCCAGAUCCUUCUCUUUGGCUGAGUUCUCAUUGUUAAAGCCACGCGCUGGAUCCUGCAGGACCCAGGAGCCAAGAAAGCCUGCAGACGGGCAGCCGUGGCUCAGGUGUUCCCCUUGCACAGGUGGACAGAGGAUCAGGGUCCACGGGGCUCACCCUGCCACGUCCCCACCCAUUCGGCAGAAGGGGAAGUUGAGGCCCAGAGGCAGGGAGAGCUUCCCCCAGGGACACACAGCACAGGAGAGCCAGCUGGGAGCCCCUCCCCUGACUCCCUGCCCGGUGCUCCUGAUGCCCCCCGGCCGGCUGGCUGUGGGGGUGUCUGAGGGUGGAGUGGCUAUGGGAAGAUGGCAGGGGGAGGCACAGCCACCCUUGCAGACACCCCAUUCCCAGCACUCCUUCCUCACACCCAGACCCCUUGCCUCCCACCCAGACAUGAGCACCAGCCUCCAGGAAGGCCAGGAGGACGGGCCGGCAGGAUGGAGAGCGAAUCUGAAGCCCGUGGACAGGAGAAGCCCAGCUGAGAGGACUCUGAAGCCCAAGGAACCACGGGCCCUGGCAGAGCCGAGGGCGGGGGAGGCCCCCAGGAAGGUCUCAGGCAGCUUUGCUGGGAGUGUCCACAUCACCCUGACCCCCGUGAGGCCUGACAGGACCCCACGCCCAGCCAGCCCAGGACCCAGCCUCCCAGCCAGGUCCCCCUCCCCACCCCGCCGCAGGAGACUGGCCGUCCCUGCCAGCCUCGACGUUUGUGACAACUGGCUUCGGCCGGAGCCCCCUGGCCAGGAAGCCCGAGUGCAGAGCUGGAAGGAGGAGGAGAAGAAACCUCACCUUCAGGGCAAACCAGGGAGACCCUUGUCCCCGGCCAAUGUCCCUGCUCUGCCUGGCGAGACGGUGACCUCCCCAGUCAGGCUGCACCCCGACUACCUCUCCCCGGAGGAGAUACAGAGGCAGCUGCAGGACAUCGAGAGGCGGCUGGACGCCCUGGAGCUCCGCGGCGUGGAGCUGGAGAAGCGACUGCGGGCGGCCGAGGGAGAUGACGCUGAGGAUAGCCUCAUGGUGGACUGGUUCUGGCUCAUUCACGAGAAGCAGCUUCUGCUGAGACAGGAGUCAGAGCUGAUGUACAAGUCCAAGGCCCAGCGUCUGGAGGAGCAGCAGCUGGACAUCGAGGGCGAGCUGCGCCGGCUCAUGGCCAAGCCCGAGGCUCUGAAGUCACUGCAGGAGCGGCGGCGGGAGCAGGAGCUGCUGGAGCAGUACGUGAGCACCGUGAACGACCGCAGUGACAUCGUGGACUCGCUGGACGAGGACCGGCUCCGGGAACAAGAGGAGGAUCAGAUGCUGCGGGACAUGAUUGAGAAGCUGGGCCUCCAGAGGAAGAAGUCCAAGUUCCGCUUGUCCAAGAUCUGGUCACCAAAAAGCAAAAGCAGCCCCUCCCAGUAGUAGCCAGUAGGGCCGUGGGCUCGGCCCGGACCUGGCAUCCGGACUUGGACUCGGGGCCAUGGGCUUGGCCCGGACCCGGAACCCGGACUUGUACUCGGGGCCGUGGGCUCGGCCCGGACCCGGCAUUCGGACUUGGACUCGGGAAGGGCCUCCUGUCCCUACAAGGGGCAUGUGGACAGCAGGGACCUGCGCUACCGUCUGUGGUCUCAAUAAAGAAACCGACCACAUGGCCCCGGA